GACUCGAAGUGGACUUCCGGGUCACGGCGGAGCUGGCUCUCACGUGGAGGCGGGGAAAUUUCGCCCACCGGUGAGUGCCAGGGCGCGUUGCAGGCGGGCCGGCGCGGGGUGUGGAGAUUGCACCAGAGGAAGUGCGCGGCGGGGAAGAUGGGGAAAUGCGGUCCACCCACAUCCCUGAAUCCGACCCCUCCAGUCGGUGUGCGCCCGCUCCGGCCUGAGGCCGCCGCCUCCAGAAAGUUUUCCCGCCUCAGAGCCGGCCCUGGGACCCCACGUAAUCCCUCCCAGUCUGUUGAUGCGGAGGCUUGGGCCCAUGGGAGCCUUGGAGGUACGGAUCUUACUUCCUGGCUCCCGCGCGUCCUGCUGGUGAUCCUGCCGGGGGAGUGGGGUGUUGCUGCACAGGCUUUGGAGUCCUGUGGGCGGAAUUCCAGUCUCCGUUUUCCACUUGCUGGCUUUGGAACCUAGGGCAAGUGAAUUAUUGUAGUCUCUGGAGCUUGCGAGGUCGGGUAUUCACAAAGAUCUUCACAAGGCUGUCCCUGGAAUUUAAAAGCGGUUUUGGAGAAAGCGUUUGCGUUUGCAGGAGAUGCACUGUAACGUUCUUUUCCUUUCUCCUUGAAAGAGUGAAUGCAUUUGGUCGCAGGGCUAAAGAGGAGGAUGCUAUACUUUUCUAAAUGGCAAGAGAUGGGGAGAGAAGGGGAUUAAGAGUUGACCCGCAACCUCCCGGUGGAUUCUUUGUUCUUACCAGAUCUCUUGGCCACUCCCCUAUUCUGAAGUCGUCUUGGCUCUCUUGACUGCUCCCCUAUUCUGAAGUCGUCUUGGCUCUCUUGACUGCUCCCCUAUUCUGAAGUCGUCUUGGCUCUCCUGACUACACUAUUUCAAGGAAUGAUCACCAAGACACACAAAGUAGACCUUGGGCUCCCAGAGAAGAAAAAGAAGAAGAAAGUGGUCAAAGAACCAGAGACUCGAUACUCAGUUUUAAACAAUGAUGAUUACUUUGCUGAUGUUUCUCCUUUAAGAGCUACAUCCCCCUCUAAGAGUGUGGCCCAUGGGCAGGCACCUGAGAUGCCUCUAGUGAAGAAAAAGAAGAAGAAAAAGAAGGGUGUCAGCACCCUUUGCGAGGAGCAUGUAGAACCUGAGACCACGCUGCCUGCUAGACGGACAGAGAAGUCACCCAGCCUCAGGAAGCAGGUGUUUGGCCACUUGGAGUUCCUCAGUGGGGAAAAGAAAAAUAAGAAGUCACCUCUAGCCAUGUCCCAUGCCUCUGGGGUGAAAACCUCCCCAGACCCUAGACAGGGUGAGGAGGAAACCAGAGUUGGCAAGAAGCUCAAAAAACACAAGAAGGAAAAAAAGGGGGCCCAGGACCCCACAGCCUUCUCGGUCCAGGACCCUUGGUUCUGUGAGGCCAGGGAGGCCAGGGAUGUUGGGGACACUUGCUCAGUGGGGAAGAAGGAUGAGGAACAGGCAGCCUUGGGGCAGAAACGGAAGCGGAAGAGCCCCAGAGAACACAAUGGGAAGGUGAAGAAGAAAAAAAAAAUCCACCAGGAGGGAGAUGCCCUCCCAGGCCACUCCAAGCCCUCCAGGUCCAUGGAGAGCAGCCCUAGGAAAGGAAGUAAAAAGAAGCCAGUCAAAGUUGAGGCUCCGGAAUACAUCCCCAUAAGUGAUGACCCUAAGGCCUCCGCAAAGAAAAAGAUGAAGUCCAAAAAGAAGGUAGAGCAGCCAGUCAUCGAGGAGCCAGCUCUGAAAAGGAAGAAAAAGAAGAAGAGGAAAGAGAGUGGGGUAGCAGGAGACCCUUGGAAGGAGGAAACAGACACGGACUUAGAGGUGGUGUUGGAAAAAAAAGGCAACAUGGAUGAGGCGCACAUAGACCAGGUGAGGCGAAAGGCCUUGCAAGAAGAGAUCGAUCGCGAGUCAGGCAAAACGGAAGCUUCUGAAACCAGGAAGUGGACGGGAACCCAGUUUGGCCAGUGGGAUACUGCUGGUUUUGAGAACGAGGACCAAAAACUGAAAUUUCUCAGACUUAUGGGUGGCUUCAAAAACCUGUCCCCUUCGUUCAGCCGCCCCGCCAGCACGAUUGCAAGGCCCAACAUGGCCCUCGGCAAGAAGGCGGCUGACAGCCUGCAGCAGAAUCUGCAGCGGGACUACGACCGGGCCAUGAGCUGGAAGUACAGCCGGGGAGCCGGCCUCGGCUUCUCCACCGCCCCCAACAAGAUCUUUUACAUUGACAGGAACGCUUCCAAGUCAGUCAAGCUGGAAGAUUAAACUCUAGAGUUUUGUCCCCCCAAAACUGCCACAAUUGCUUUGAUUAUUCCAUUUAUGCUGGAGAUUACAAAUUUUUUUUGUGAAAAAAUCAGAUCUUGGUGAGGACCUCGAGCAGUAAGAUAUAAAUAACUCCCAUAAGCUUAGCGUUCCAGUAAUGGAACACUAGGCAUAAAUGGUUUAUUCAGUUGUGCAAAUGAAAGCCAUCUGACAGUUGGCUCACAUUGAACACCUGUGGAGAUUAAGGACGAGGACAACUAUAUUGAUGGGCUUGGAUGAACUGGGGCAGGGCAGCUCAUAUUUCGGGAGCCAGGAGAACGAGUGAGUGCUAAAACCUCCUGUUUUCUGUGUUAAACAUUCCGUCCCUGUUUGAGACAUCAGUAUGUACAGUUAACUUUUGUUGAGUGUUUAGCAGGUACUAGGGACAUACUAGUGUUUUCCUUAAUGUAUUUAAUCUUCAUAAUUAUGAAAUGGGUGCUAUUAUUAGCCCCAUCUUAUAGAUGAGGCAACUGAGGUUCAGGGAUAAAGUAAUAAAAUUGCCUGGGGUCACCCAGCCACUAAGUGCAGGGUGUUGUACUUUUGUACCCGAAGCCCUAAGUUCACUAUUCGCCACUCUGAAUGUCCCCUUUAGGGAAUUUCCACCAGAAUCCUCGUUGGGGAUUGAAAUGUCUUUAGAUGGAGGAAAAAGUUUUAUGACAAGUCUGCAUCUCUGAUAAAAAGUGGAGUGAAUGAGGAACGGAGAAUCGCAAACUCCUUUUCCUUCCUUUUCCUUUCCCCUGUCAUAGAGCAGCUGUAGGCAGAGAGGUGUCUGAGUUGUUACCAAACACAUGUGACUGAGCUGCUGCUGCUGGGAAAUGUGCCUCUAAACCAGUCCUGCCUUUUCCACUGGUGUCCCUUCGGCCCUAAGUGCUGAGGUAGGAUUUUUGUGCUUUGACUGGAUUCUGAACAAGGCAUUUUAGGAAGAGUGGUUAGUCCCGCAAAUGAAUCAAUGGCAGAUCCCAGGGACGUGUGUGUGUGUUUUGAGAUAGGCUCUCACUCUGUCACCCAGGCUGGAGUGUAGUGGCAUAUCACGGCUUGUUGCAACCACUACCUAUCCAGCUUAAGUGAUCCUCCCACCUCAGCCUCCCAAGUAGCUGGGACUGUGGGUGUGCACCACAACAACCAGCUAGUGUUUAAAAUUUUUUGUAGAGAUGGGGUCUCACUAUAUUGUCCAGGCUAGUCCCAAACUCCUGGACUCAACUCAUGCUCCUGCCUCAGCCCCCAAGAGCUGGGAUCACAGGUGUGAGCCACUGUGCCCAGCCCCAGGGAUGUGUCUGAUGAGAUUCUUUUUUAUCACAAGGAAGAGAAUCCCAGGUGACUUCUGUAGGUGGAUAUUGAAUGCCAGGAGGAGAUGAACGUGUGGAGAUGACACGGGAAGUUGCCUCAUCGGCUGUGGGGACAGCGUUUCCAAGCCUGGACUCUACAGCAAGCCUCAAAGAGCUCCAGGUCCAGUGGCCCAAGUCGCAUGUGACCAUCUGUGACCACCUUCUUUCCACUCACCUAGCUUUUUGCAUCCCAAAAUACAGGUUCUGACUGGGACAUUUUCACGAUCGUUUGGCCUGAACAUGCCUCCUACAGACAUCCCAGCCCAGGCAGGCCUCGAUGGCCAGAAAGUUCAGUCUCACGUGGCAGGAAGGCCUGAUUAGGGCCUGGUUCAACAGCUCGCCAAGGAAGCAUUCUCUCCAUCAUCUCCAGUGUUGGCUUCAUCAAGGCUAGUACAAAGAUGGCAGUAACAGUUCCAGGCAGCAUAUCAAGACCCUAGAACAUUCCAGAGGAAGAAAAGCCUUUUUGUGUCUCAAGGAAACUUCCAGAAGCCUCCAUUGCUGGGCAAUGAGUCAUCUGCCCAUAGCUGCACCCGCCCCUGUCAUGGGAAGGCUGGUGAUUCCCUUCAGUCAAGAAGAGUGGAUGCUGGUGAAGUGGCCAUGGUGUCCACAGCUGCCCAUUGGGCAGAGGUGAGGCAGGCACUUCAGGCAGUUUCCCUGGCUCUGAACCCUGAUCCGCAAGCAUUGGCCAGGUCAAUAGUUGGACAAGUAUGUGCUACAAGGACCUACUUGGGCCACUUCCCUCAGGACGUGAACUUGUCCUGCCUUUCUUUCCUGGAUUCAACCUUGAGAUACAUAAUGGGAGAGGCCGUGGAAAGCCCAAGAGGCAGUGUUCUGGAUUUGAGUGAGUGCCUUCUGGGCACCUCCUCCUUUGAUGGAGAAACAAAUCCCUCCUGACCUUGAGCAACACUACAGGAAUGUGCCUGGUGUAAACAGGAACCAGCCGUUCGUUUCUUUUUUUUUGAGAUGGAGUCUCACGGUCGCGCAGGCUGGAGUGUGGUGGCGUGAUCUCGGCUCAUUGUAACCUCUGCUUCCUGGGUUCAAGCGAUUCUUGUGCCUCAGUCUCCUGAGUAGCUGGAAUCGGCCGUUUACUACUCAUAGUUUUUAUCUUGCCAAGAGGUCACCCUGACGUUGGCCUGCCUUAGCUCUGUUAAAAAGGUUGUGCUCUGCCAGGUGCGGUGACUCACGCCUGUAAUCCCAGCACUUUGGGAGGCCAAGGUGGGCGGAUCACGAGGUCAAGAGUUCGAGACCAGCCUGACCAACAUGGUGAAACCCCGUCUCUACUAAAAAUACAAAAAUUAGCUGGGUGGGUGUGGUGUCACGGGCUUGUAAUCCCGGCUACUCAGGAGGCUGACAGGAGAAUCGCUUGAACCCGGGAGGUGGAGGUUGUAGUGAGCUGGGAUGGUGCCACUGCACACUCUAGCCCCGGGCAACAGAAUGAGACUCUGUCUCAAAAACAAACAAAAAAAAACUGUCUUUGGGUGAUUGUGGAGAGGUGAUCAUAUGUCCGCUGUGUUGCUCCCAUCCAAGCCCUGGUGACUGGUAGCUCUCAUGAGGGUGUGAUGGUCAGGCCUUGCCCCUGGUGUAAAUUCUGUCUGUAAUAGGCUGUGACUUUCUAACUCAACAUCACCACUGGCUUAGGAGUUCCAUUUGCACAGGGGGAGCUUUAUUGCUUUUCUAUAUACAUAAGAACUUUACGUCUCACCAGUGGAGGUUGGGCAGCCAAGACACCACAAUGCUGGGUGUCUUCAGAAUGGACUUAAUCUUGUCCUUUUGCUUUCUGCCAGUGCAGAUCACCAUCUCUCAGAUGAGCAGGACCCCACCCUCUGGCAGUCUUGUCUUGGGAGAAUCACUCUGAGCUCCCAUCCUUUGUAAAUUAACAUUGGUUUGAGCACCACCCUCCAUCACGGCUGCAGUGAGCCAUGAUUGCACCACUGUGUUCCAGCCUGGGUGACAGAGCAAGACCCCAUUCCAAAAAAAAAAAAAAAUUUGCCAAAUAGACACAGUCCUCACAAAAGAAGUUGGCAGAAUAACACCCCUUCCUACCACAUCUCCUCAGAACCUGUGUAUUUGUUAGGUUACGAAACAAAAGGGAAUUAAGUUUGCUAAUCAGCUGACCUUAAAACAGGAAGAGGAUCCCGUGUUUCUGGGUGGGCCGGAGGAAUCACAAAGAUCCCUAAAUGUGGAAGAGGAAGGCAAAAAAGAGUCCACAUCAAAGAGACUUAAGAAAGACUUGACUAGACACUGCUGGUUUUGAAGAUGGGAAGGGAAGGGUCAGAAGCCAAGGAAUGUGUGUGCUGUCUAGAAGCUGGAAAAGGCAAGGAAGUAGAUUCUCCCCUAGAGCCUCCCAGAAGGAGCGUAGCCCUGCUGAUGCCUUAAUUUUAGCUCAGUGAGACCAGGCGGACUUAAGACCUAUAGAACCGUCAGAUGACAACAUUAUGUUUUAAGCCGCUACAAUUGUGGCAAUUUGUUAAAGUAACAAUAGAAGACCUAAUGUAAGUAAGUCUCAUGUGGAAGUUGCCAUGGUUUUGUUUUUCUUUCUUUUUUUUUUUUUGAGACAGUCUCACUCUCACUCCACGCCCAGGCUGGAGUGCAGAGGCGUGAUCUCAGCUCACUGCAACCUCCACCUCCAGGGUUCAAGCGAUUCUCCUGCCUCAGCCUCCUGAGAAGCUGGGAUUACAGGUGAGCACCACCACACCCAGCUAAUUUUUUUUUGUAUUUUUAGUAGAGAUGGAGUUUCACCAUGUUGGCCAGGAUGGUCUUGAUCUCUUGGCCUCAUGAUCCACCUACCUCAGCCUCCCAAAGUGUUGGUAUUACAGGCAUGAGCCACCGCACCCAGGCCCCAUCAUUUUUAUUUUCUACAAUUCUGGCUGACAUCUUAUUGCUCCAUCCUUGCUAAUGAUAGACUUCAUCUCACAUAGACCAGUGUUUUCAGAGACCGGCUUAUUGAUUCAGUAAAGGGCUGGGGGAAACUGCACACACAAGGACAUAUAAAAUCUAAGCCUCUGCCUGGGCCACAUGACAGGAUUCAGAAGCACCUUUGAUAUAAUGGGUGCCCGACCUCAUGUGAAAGUCCAAGUUCAGGUGUAAUGUGAGAGCGGUAAGAAUUCACUGGCCUAGGCUUGGGAACUAAUGCUGCCCACCACGUUCAGCCUCAGAGGAGAAGAAAUGACUUGAAGAACAUAAUUUGUGAAUUUGCCAAUUGUUUUUCAUUUUAUAGCAUCACACAGUAAAAGUAGAUAAAAUAAUUUUAAUGAAAAUACUUCUGUGGGCCAGGUGCGGUGGCUUACGCCUGUAAUCCCAGCACUUUGGGAGGCCGAGGCGGCGGAUCACCUGAGGUCAGGAGUUCUAGACCAGCCUGACCAACAUGGAGAAACCCCAUCUCUACUAAAAAUACAAAAUUAGCUGGGUGUGGUGGCGCACUCCUGUUAUCCCAGCUACUCAGGAGGCUGAGGCAGGAGAAUUGCUUAGACUCGGGAGGCGGAGGUUGGGGUGAGCCGAGAUCACGCCAUUGUACUCCAGCCUGGGCAACAAGAGUGAAACUGUCUCAAAAAAAAGAAAAAAAAACAGAAUUUUGUGAAAUAAAGGCCACUUGGGAGUAUCUGAGCCACCCCA